GAGCCCACGACCUGGGCUUCUCGCCCUGCCCUACUGCUUGCUGGUUCGUGGCCGGGCCGCGCCUCUUCUGGGCAGAGGGCACCGCCGACGGCCAGGCCGCAGAGGGGGCUUGCGAGGAUCGGAAGCUGGUCAGCAGCUGUUGGGAUGUGUACAUCGUGAAGCCCACCUGGUGGCCGUGGUUAAAUUGUAUCCAAAUGAAAUGACACUGAUCACUGCGUCCCCUGCAGCAGAUGCUGUCUCAGUCAUGUAACUUGGAUCCACUUACAGAAACUUAUGGGAUUCCUUUCUACCUACAAUACCUCGCCCACUGGCCAGAGUAUUUCAUUGUUGCAGAGGCACCUGGUGGAGAAUUAAUGGGUUAUAUUAUGGGUAAAGCAGAAGGCUCAGUAGCUAGGGAAGAAUGGCACGGGCACGUCACAGCUCUGUCUGUUGCCCCAGAAUUUCGACGCCUUGGUUUGGCUGCUAAACUUAUGGAGUUACUAGAGGAGAUUUCAGAAAGAAAGGGUGGAUUUUUUGUGGAUCUCUUUGUAAGAGUAUCUAACCAAGUUGCAGUUAACAUGUACAAGCAGUUGGGCUACAGUGUAUAUAGGACGGUCAUAGAGUACUAUUCGGCCAGCAACGGGGAGCCUGAUGAGGACGCUUAUGAUAUGAGGAAAGCACUUUCCAGGGAUACUGAGAAGAAAUCCAUCAUACCAUUACCUCAUCCUGUGAGGCCUGAAGACAUUGAAUAACCCUGGGCAGUGGUUCUUAGGCAGAUACUCUAGAUGCUUUAUGGACAAUAUUAUUUUCAUUGGAUGAUUCUGGAGCUCUAUUAGGAGAAAAGUAAUCAUUUUAGGUCUUAAAGACUUCAAGAAAAUACAGGUUAUCAAUUUAUUUUAAAUCUCAUUGUUUCCAGUUAGCAAUAUCAUACCUAUUAAAGCUGUUCAUUGUAACAAAAUUCAAUCAAAAAGGCAGCUAGGUCAGAAGGAAACAUACCACUCUCAUGGUUCAUAGUAUUCACUGUAUGUAUGCUAGGGAAAAGACUUGCUCCAGUCUCCUCCUCAGUUCUGUGCCUGAGAACCACUGCUGCAUAUAUUUGUUUUUAAAUUUUGUAUUGAACUGUUAAUUGAAGCUUUAAAAGCAUAUAUGAAAUGUAUAAAUCUAAGAUGUAUAAUACAUUAUUGACUCUAUGAA